AGCGAGACUCUGUCUCAAAAAUAAAUAAAUAAAUAAAUAAAAAGAAAAGAAAAGAACAUUUAGUGAAAGGAGCAAGGAAGAGAAGGCAUUCUGGGCAGACCCCGGCCCCCAGGGCACAGGCGUGCAGUGUUUCCCUUCCAGGGUUUGGUGGACACUUGGAGGGACCAGGUCGGGGUGUGGCCUGGGAGGGGUGGCCAAGGUCCAGGGGUCAGGGUCACUUCGGGGAAGUCCAAGGGGCAGCGCGGAGCCACCGCUGUGGACAUGGGAGGAGCCUACUAGCCAGCAUGGCCCAAAGGAAGGAGGGGCUGAGGGUCAGAGGUCAUGGGAGAGAAGAGGGAGUGGGGCAGACCCUCUCCCAAGGCCAUGGGGUGGGGGAGAAACAGCGCCUUAGGGCCUGUCCUGAUCCUCCUCCAGAGCCUGCUCAGAGUGGGAGCAGCCCCUCCUCCCUUCCCCUCCACCACCCAGGCGCAGGUGCGGCCUCUCCCUGGCCCGGGGACCUGCGUGAGGUCAGCCCUCAAAGCGCUGUCCCUUCUGGCUCACCUGGGCCCAGGGUGAGGCCCGACCCCACGGUGGACCCUGAGUCACUGCAGCUUCUGUGCCCAGCUCAGGAACAGAGCAGCCUUCAAGGCCAGGACUGGGGAGGGGCUCGGCUUUUCCGGCCCUUGGACGCCACUCAACUCUUCCUGCCCGUGUGUUGGCAAAGAACUAGCACGGCCUCUGAAGCACUGAAAAGACAAGGGCUACCUCUUUUCCAGAAGGUCCCAGAGCCCACCAUGAGCAGGCAGUGUUUGGGAAAAGCCCGGGGAGGUGGCAGGGGCUCCGAGGAGCGGGGGAUUCUAAGGGGUUAUAGCUGCGCUGAGCCCCGGGCUCCUCAGAAGCCUCAGAAGGAGAAGGGGGCUCCUUUGGGGGCAUCCUCCCUGCAUCCGGGGUGUUGCAGGGUGACCUCCCGUAGUGCCAGCAGGGGCGGCCCCUCGGUCUGGCCAGAGAAGCCCAGCCACUGUCCCGUAUGGUGGAUGUCAGGCCCAGUGCCGUGUUUCCGAAGGAGGGAAGGGGUGAGAGGCAGCAGCCAGACACCCCGCUGAGCCCGCCCCGACCCUGAGCACGUGGGAGCUGGAGACGGUGUCACACACUCGGCCUGGCUUUGGGACCAUCCCUAGGGCUUCUGUGGGGAGGAGGAAGGAGGAGCAGACGUGGAAGGGCUGCCAGGGCCCCAGCAGAUGGGGUCGGGGGCGGAGGAGAGCCAGGAAAGUGUGGGCGCCUGGGGGAGUCACAGAUGGAGGUCUGGUACCUAGAGCCUGGAGAACGACGGCUCUCGGGACAGAGGGCCUCAGACUCUGGCACACCAGCCGUACCUAUGACAAGCUCCAUGGGGGAAGAACCAGGCACCUGGAUGCAUGGCUGUGAGGCCCCCACCCCACAGGGGCCUCAGAGGCACAGGCUCCAGGCUCCAGCGGGGAGGGCGCUGCAUCCCACCCUGGGAGCAUGGCUAUGAGGCCCCCACCCCACAGGGGACCCAGAGGCACAGGCUCCAGGCUCCAGCGGGAAGGGCCCUGCUCCCCACCCCCAUCCCCCGCCUCAGGCUUCACUGAGAUGGGCCCCGGGGACCCCGGGAGCUUUCUGUGACUGCUCGGCAAUGGGUUCCCCAAGGCCUGGCACAGGCUUUCCUUAGAGCCAGGCUGUGGACCCAAAGCCUUGGGCCAAGUCUCAGGACCAGAUGGGCGGCUCUGGAGAGGACCCCACAGUCCAGGGUGAGGCGCGCCCCGCUGGGGGCAGCGCUGCCUGUGGAGAGGACCCCACAGUCCAGGGUGAGGCGCGCCCCGCUGGGGGCAGCACUGCCCGUGGCCGUCUCCAUCCAUCUCACCCUGACGCAAGGCCGGCUUCCUCUGCGUCCAGUGGUCGGGGCCUUGGAGAGGCCAGCAGGGCCCGUGGGGGUCGCGUUUCUUCCCUGUGGCAUCAGCUCUUUUCCCAGCAGGCCUCUUUGCAGCUGGAUGCAGCAGCCAAGCCCUGGAGUCUUUGGAAAACUGUGGCCUGGCGGGGGCCCAGGCAAUGCCACCUUACAGGGGACACCCACACAGGCGGUCCCGAGGAGGGGUGUGCUGCCGCCCUGAGCUCAGCCAGGCAUCACCGUGGUGUCACCGUCAGCUCGGGUGGCACCUCCCGGGCUGCCCUCUCGGCUGCCACUUCUCAUGAAACUGACAGGGACUGAACACGAAUGAUGUGGCUUAUAGCUGGGUGCCCCCACCCUGACCACAGGUGCCACGCGACGGGAGCCACAUUCUCUUCCUGAUUCUAACUCCACGGGUACAGAGACAGAAGCUGCCAUCUUUAGAAAUAAAACUUUUUUCUAACUACAAAAUAAUACAGUUUAAUAUAGGAAAUGUGGAAAAUGGGGUAUUCGGGGUGGAUAUUGAGAAGAGAGAAGCAACACCAAUUCUAUGUGCGAGACGCUGGCACUUCCCAGCGUAGCCUUGUGUUCCUGACCCUGGGGUGGCCUGAGCGUGGCCUGUGGGGCCCGUGUCCAGGUGCGGAGGGGGCCCUGAGUCGUGCGGGGCAAGUGGUCAGGGCCCCAGGCCCAGGCUGCCUGGAGCGAGAUGACUGGGCCUGGCCCCUGGGGACUUGCUCUGACAAAACCCCCCGGUCCCCACUCCUGAGCCCCUGCAGGAGCAGCCCUGGGAACAUGGGGAGCAGCUCCUUCUGCCUAUGUGCUCCGGACUCAGGAACUCUGGAGAGAAGAAACACAACCCCACAGGCCCCGCCUGCCUCUCCUGCAGUCUUGAGGCCCCAGGGAAAGCCCCCACUGCAGGCAGGGGGACGUGGCUGGCCUGGUCUGCCCCCAGCUGAGCCUCACCUGAGGGAGAGCUGGGGUGGGCCGCCUCGUUUACGACCGUGUAGUCGUCUUUUGCACACAAAGCCAUGUGAGUCCGUACGUGAGUCCUGUGGAAAGACAAGACAUGGAAUAGGAGUGACGUCCGUCCCCAGGCAUGAAGUGGAGAGCAUCACGCUGUGUGAGUUAAACACUGGCCAAGCACGGUGUGAGUCGGAGCCGGGGACCUGGCCAGAUGAGGGCUGCGUGCAGCUUUCACACCCCAGGCACGUGAGCACCGCCAAGCCCAGCCUCAGCCAGCAGCUGCUCUGCAAUGUGGAGUCACCAGUGGCCCCAAGGAUGGCAGGUGGGGGUGGCCUUGGGACUGAAUUAGGCCGACACCCAAGGCCUCUGUUCCUUCCCGUCCCUUCUCUCCCUUCGGAGGAUCAAAUGAGAGUUUCUAGGAAAGAAAACAUGGCCAGGCCCUCCUCCAGCGCCCAGGCAGGGCUCGAGCGGACGCCCGUGUGACCCCCACAUCCCUUCUACCCCUGUAGCUCUCUGACUCUGAUAUCCCAGUGGGAGGAACGAGGAGGGGACGGGUGAGGAGGAGGAAGAGGAGGAGACAUGAGGGUUAGGAGGAGCACAUCCUGAGUUUGUGAGGCUUCACUGACCUCUGGCCUCACAAACACACACAGGCCUGAGCUCCGGAUAUUUCUCCUGUUCUGGAGACAGUGAGAAGUGAAAGAGAAAUGGCUGCCCCUGCACCACUUACCGCGAAGGAGGCUCAAGGCUGGGGGGCCCCUCUGCCUUCCAGUGACCGCCCGUGUCACAUCCUGACCCGCUCAGCAGAGACGGCCAGAGGCAUGGAUGCACGCUGACUCGUGGACGGCCGCUGUUUGACGAGACCAUCAAGGAGGGAGGAGCACCCGUGGAAAGGCGUGGCAGGGUGGUCGGGGCAGAGGUGUACAUCAGCCUAUCCAAUGCUCACGGCUGGAGGACGCCGCGCCCUGUGAAUGCUCACUGAGGACCAUCCCGGGCACUGGGGCUCUCCAUGAGAACACAGCAGGUCCCUCCGACCGCAGUCGGCCUCUCCAGCCUGCCAUGCCUCUGGCCAUGAGGCGACCCGCUGGAGUGAUGGAUUCCCGUCACUACCACCCACAGGGCGAGGGGGUGCAUUGGUCUGCUUGGGCCGCUGUAACAAAAUGCCACAGCCUGGAUGAGUGACUGACAUUGCUUCCCCACCGUUCUGGAGGCUGGAGGCCCGAGAUCGAGGUCCCUGACACUAUUUCAGUGAUGCCAGAGCCCAGGAGGAGUCGACCAAGCCCCAGCGUGGCCAUAAGCACCUUCGCAGGACCACGGAGUCGCUGCAGGUGUUCAGCCCUGUUGAGAGUGGGAGUCGGUGUCGAUGGUCACAGCUCAGUAACUCAUCGUCACCAGCGAGUACCACAGAGCAGACACAACUGCACUUCUCUGUAGAGCCUCCAGUCGAUACUGAGAGCCACUGGGGCGUCUGACACCCAAGGGUGCAGACAUUCACUCCAAGUCCAGAGACCGCGCCCUUUCUAAGGCCCUGUCUCACAGUCGCCCCGUGCUCAUUGUGCCGGAUGUUUCCACAGCCACAGAGACGGUGCGUGAAGGUGAGGUGCAGCCUAGUGCAUAUGACUGACAGAAACGUGAAGCCACAGUGGACGCCUGGAUGAGACACAGAUCACCUUCCAAAUCUGAGUGUGGCCUUGGGACCAACCAGGCAGCCAGGGAGAAGGCAGAGACCAGAGGGAACCCAGGUGCCCUCAAUCCCAGCCUCCUCUAUCCCAGCCUCCCAAUCCCAGCCUCCCCAAUCCCAGCCUCCUAAUCCCAGCCUCCUCCAUCCCAGGACCCCCACUCCCAGCCUCCCGAUCCCAGCUUCUCUGAUCCCAGCCUCCCCUAAAACCCAGACUCUAUGAAUCCCAGCCUCUGAGGUGGGAACUGUUAGUAACCCCACUCCAUGGACAAGAAAGCUGGGGCCUGGCGAGGCUAACAGACUAUCCUGAUGGUGUGAGGGAGGGAUCGGCCUCUGAGGGCUGCUUCCACCCAUCUCACCAGUGGCUGCAGGCUCCAGGCGCCACUUUCCUUGAGUCUAUGUUCUUUCCAAGCAUCCUGCAGCUCCAGAAGCUCUGGAGCCGCCAGCACUGAGAGAAGCGAUGGAGCUGCAUGCAGGGAAACUUUGUUGACAGCGGUGUCUGGAUGGACCAGCAGAGGGCACUCUCACCCACGGGGAAAAUCGUGCGCCCGGCCUCGUCCACCGCCAGAAGACGCCGCUACACAAUGGAGUCUCGCUCUGUCGACCAGGCUGGAGUGCAAUGGUGCGAUCUCGGCUCACUGCAAUCUCUGCCUCCCGGUGAGAGGUGAAGCCAGCUGGACUUCCUGGGUCUAGUGGGGACUUGGAGAACUUUUCUGUCUAGCUAAAGAUUUGUAAAUGCACCAAUCAGUGCUGUGUCUAGCUAAAGUUUGUAAACGUACCAAUCAGCACUCUGUAAAAAUGGGCCAAUCAGCACUCUGUAAAAUGGACCAAUCAGCACUCUGUAAAAUGGACCAGUCAGCAGGAUGUGGGCGGGGUCAAAUAAAGGAAUAAAAAGCUGGUAGCCGAGCCGGCAGUGGCAAACCGUUUGGGUCCUUCUCGGUACCCUGGUGGCUUUGUUGUUUUGCUC